CGUGCAACUGGUUAAAAUCGAAGUAUAUCUUAUGUUGGUAUAUGAAAGAGGCCUAGGUCUUAUCACAGGGGUGCCUGUGACCUUCCUUGAGUGUCUCACAGAGUUGUUAGAAUUGGGCCUGAGUUUAAAUCCCUACUUUGUCACCUACUCGUUUAGGGAUUAAAAAAAAUUCCUCAAGCUUUCUGGGCUUGAAUUUCCUCAAAGGUAAAAUGGAACUAAUAAUACCUAUCUCACAGGUUUUUGGAACGCUUAAAUGAGGUAAUGUGUAUAAAGUGCGUGGUCCAUGGAGAGUAAUCAAUAAAUAAUACAGCAAAUAUUUAAUGUAGUGCUUUUAGCAUGUUACAAGGCAAUGUUUCAGGCACUUUACAUGAUCCUAUGAGAUAGAUACUAUUGUCAUCUUUAAAACAAGCCUAUGAGAUAGAUGCUAUUAGUAGCCACAAUAUAUAGAUGUGGAAAUUGAGAUAUAGAAAGGCAAAGCUUGUCCAAAUUUACAUGGCUGGUAGAUGGUGGAGCCAGGAUUAGAACCCAGGCAGCAAGUGAAUAGAUAGUUUCUAUAUCCCUGGUUUCUUGUGUCUUGUUGGUUUUGGGAGACUGAUGAAGCAUAGUGAUGUAGAGAUACUAGAAACUUAGACCGAAGUACCAGUUCUGCUAUAUACUAGCAGUGUGACAUUGAGAAAGUGAGCCUUAGUUUCCUCAUCUGUAAAAUGGUGGUUUUACCUACCCAACCGUGAACUAUGUGGCACUAUAAAAAUGUUGGGAUUGACACAUUUGAGCAUGUAUUGGGGGCCCUGUCCUAGAUGUGGGUAAAAUCUGUUGUGAAGCCUGAGGUCUUAUACAUACUGUGCAGUGCAAGCACCCAUAAUAGGAAUGUCGAACACUGCUAGUGAGGUAGAAGGCAUAGGCAAAAUGGCGGAAAUUCCAUCCCCUUUAUCACCCACUCUAUCCCCCACCCUCAGCGAGCACUUUUAAUAAAAUAAUAUGUACCAUAUUGGUAUUGUUUCCCAAACUUUGGUACUGUCACAUAUGCAAGAUAAUUUGAUAAGCAAAUGAACAUUAAAAAAUUCUCCCCAAAUUUUCACACACAUACAUAUUUGAAUGAAACAAGUUCAUUUAAUUUAAAUUAGGAGAAAAACUUAACAUCUCAAAACUGAUUUCACAGAUAUUAUUGCUAAAAAAUAAAGGACAAGAAAAGUAAGUCAAUUCAAAGACCAAUAUUAGGUAAAUAGUACAGGUGGAUGAAGAUAAUUCUGAAAGUGGUACUUGGAUGACUGAAGACUGGGAAGUUAUGAACUAAAAUAAAUAUGAGUGCUUUUGCCCCCAGUAUAAAAUGUUUUUAUCUUAAAAGUGGCAUUUGUGAAAGCAUUUGGUUAGAACGUAUAUACAAAAUCCACUUACAUGUUGGGCUUUGUUUAUUACCUUUUGAGAGAUAACUUCCUGAGACAUUGAGCCUGUAGUCAUUACCCCUACAAGGUUCUGAAGAAGAGGGGUGUCUUAUUAUCUUGGGUCCAGGAACUUGCUAACCACUACUAUAGUAGUUUGGCAUUGUGGGAAUUUAUUUUCCUCAGCCUUUACAUAAAAGUUUACCCAGAUUUACCUAGAUUCUAGCUUGUGCUUUUUCCUCCAACAGUUGCUGAUGGGGAGAGGAAAAAAUAGCCACUAUUCAGGUUCCCUGUGAGUUAACUGCUGCUGUACAAAGGCAGGUGUAAUAUUUUCUCUGUAUUAAAGGUCUUCUCUGUUGGUUGAAAUGUCUAUGAUUUUAUCUGCCUCAGUCAUUCGUGUCAGAGAUGGACUGCCACUUUCUGCUUCUACUGAUUAUGAACAAAGCACAGGAAUGCAGGAGUGCAGAAAGUAUUUUAAAAUGCUUUCGAGGAAACUUGCUCAACUUCCUGAUAGAUGUACACUGAAAACUGGACAUUAUAACAUUAAUUUUAUUAGCUCUCUGGGAGUGAGCUACAUGAUGUUGUGCACUGAAAAUUACCCAAAUGUUCUCGCCUUCUCUUUCCUGGAUGAGCUUCAGAAGGAGUUCAUUACUACUUAUAACAUGAUGAAGACAAAUACUGCUGUCAGACCAUACUGUUUCAUUGAAUUUGAUAACUUCAUUCAGAGGACCAAGCAGCGAUAUAAUAAUCCCAGGUCUCUUUCAACAAAGAUAAAUCUUUCUGACAUGCAGACGGAAAUCAAGCUGAGGCCUCCUUAUCAAAUUUCCAUGUGCGAACUGGGGUCAGCCAAUGGAGUCACAUCAGCAUUUUCUGUUGACUGUAAAGGUGCUGGUAAGAUUUCUUCUGCUCACCAGCGACUGGAACCAGCAACUCUGUCAGGGAUUGUAGGAUUUAUCCUUAGUCUUUUAUGUGGAGCUCUGAAUUUAAUUCGAGGCUUUCAUGCUAUAGAAAGUCUCCUGCAGAGUGAUGGUGAUGAUUUUAAUUACAUCAUUGCAUUUUUCCUUGGAACAGCAGCCUGCCUUUACCAGUGUUAUUUACUUGUCUACUACACCGGCUGGCGGAAUGUCAAAUCUUUUUUGACUUUUGGCUUAAUCUGUCUAUGCAACAUGUAUCUCUAUGAACUGCGCAACCUCUGGCAGCUUUUCUUUCAUGUGACUGUGGGAGCAUUUGUUACACUACAGAUCUGGCUAAGGCAAGCCCAGGGCAAGGCUCCCGAUUAUGAUGUCUGACACCAUCCUUCAGAUCUAUUGCCUUGGCUUCAGGGGGAUAAGGAGGGAACAUAUCAUAACUGCACUGUGAUGAAGAAGCUGUUCCCCACAGAGGAGAAGCUCUGCUUUCUUUCUCUCCAACUUUCCUUUUUUAAAAUCAGCAUGAUGUGCCUGUGAGCAUGGAAGAGUCCUCUCAGAAGAAUGUUGGCCAUGAGACUAUCAUUCAGAGGAGGAGGGGAUUUCUCUCUUCAAGGCCGUAACAGUGGAAGAACAGUCAUAUGCCAUUGGAAGUCUUGGCCAGCAGUCCUGAAUCCUUCCUGAAGAGUUCAGAAAAUAGAUGUGGUAUUGCUCUGAGGACCAGGCAGGAGGAACUCUACAACCUGAGUUUGCCUUUGUGAGGCAUUAGUAUAGACCAAAUAAAAAGCUGCAGAAAUUGGAAAGUUUAUGUUUUAAAUAAAUGACUGUGAUAAAUAUCAGAUUAUUUGCACACUUAUGGUACUACGAGUUUAUAAAGUCCAAGAUGGUGUGAAAUUGGUUCUUUUUACUUUUAUAUUUUUGCUUGAAUCUUAACUCUGGAAAUCACCUGAUGUAGAAGAAGACUGUGAUGAGCUCGUCUGUGGAACAUCACAAGUAUCGAAAAUACAGUAAUGGAUGUUUCCUUUCUAAUCCACAUUUAUUGUUUCUUUUGAAAUCACGUCUAAAAAAUAUGACUCACACUAUAGCCGUUGUUUCCCAAACUUCAGUCUCUUUAGUACUACUUGUAUUAUUUUCUUAAUAUUUAUCUUUUAAAUUUUAAAGUUUUUUUAAAAAAAUGAAUCCUGCUCCAAGUGGAAAACCAGUAUCAGUUUGCCAUAAAUAAAAGGUAACCACAAAAUAAGUAAGAUGAACACAAAAAAUGUUGUUCAGUUCUAGCUAGAAACUAAUGCCUAGAAAGGCUCCGAAUCUUAGGCUCUUUCUUUGUGGCAGUGAGGGAGAUGUUACCAGCACCAGCAUGAGGCACUGUCUCUGGAAUAGUCAGAGGAUAAAAGGAAACUGUAAAGGGAAUGACAUUCUCACUGUGAUUCAGCAUUAUUCUAUGUUGUGCAUCACUUAAAGACAUGUUGUGUGCCACCAGUGGCAUGGGUCCGCACUAUGGAAAUGCUUGACUGUAGUAAGAAUCAGAAGGUGGCUUUCCUAGCAACUCAUUAUUUUAUGGCUUUGAGGAAUUAAGCCCCUAGUAUCUGAGAGAACUUACUUGUUUUUUGAUAACGUUUUAAAGAUUGUUUAAGCAGUUAUGAAUUAAUAAUAUAGGAAGCACAGUUGGAUUCCACUAGCAAAAUCUAUAACUCUCAUGGUUUUGGAAGUCAUCUUCAUGGGUGAUUUUCCUUUGUUUUUUAAAGAAAAUAUUUCAAACAAGGAAUUCAUAGGAUACUGAAAUUUGAUAUCAUCCAGAAAAACAGAUCCCAUUACAUUGUAAUUGUUGUUACUAGGCAUAUUUAUUAAGUAGAGAAAUAGAGGGUAAAAAGUUAGUGAACUGUCUUGUUUGCGUGAACCAGUAUUUGUGGAUAUGUCUAGAACUGUAAAAUCUUGCUUAACUAGAACCUUAGUCUGCACCCUCCUUUUAGGAGAAUGAGGUAAAAGGAAGACAAUAAGCUUAUGAUAUCAGGGAUUCAUGUAAAACAGGAAAUAGUAGUUGGCUCCAGUCUUCUCCUCUAACAAAAGUAUGCAUAUUCUGAGAGAUACCCCAAGGCAUCACAAGAUCCUGAAUCAUCAAAACACCAUUGAAUUGUGUUGGGCAUUUUGUAGCCAGGAAAGUGAAGUGGUUCAAUUUAGAAAGGGUUUCAGGCCAGGCACGGUGACUCAGGCCUGUAAUCCCAGCACUUUGGGAGGCCGAGACAGGCAGAUCACUUGAGACCAGUAGUUUGAGAAUCAGCCUGGCCAACGUGGUGAAACCUCAUCUCUACUAAAAAUACAAAAUUUAGCUGGGUGUGGUUGCGCGUGCCUUUAGUCCCAGCUACUCGGGAGGCUGAGGCAGGAGAAUCGCUUGAACCCAGGAGGUGGAAGUUGGCAGUGAGCCAAGAUCACGCCACUGUACUCCAGCCUGGCCAACAGAGCGAGACUCUGUCUCAAAAAAGAAAGGUUUUCUAAACUAAUGGUUAAAACAGAAUUUUCUUGUAAAUAGGGAAGUUGGAGCAUUCUGGUUGAGAUUUUGCUCUGUAUUGACACAGCUCGCACCAGUUUGGUUCAGGAGCUACCUCCUUGUCAUUGAAUUGACGAGUUACAAUGUUUGGUAUUCGGAUACAUUCAGCAAGAACACUUGAAAACUCCUCACCAACUAUUUUUAAAGGCUUACUUUGUUUUUGUUUUUAUUUUUUCACUGGCUAUUUUGGAUAAGAGGAUGUUUACAUCUUAAUGUAAAAAAAUGAAAACAGGUAUAAAUGUUUUAUGUAUAGAAA